GCUUACGCCACGGCGUCUGCUGGCGGCCGCGGAGACGCAGAGUCUUGAGCAGCGCGGCAGGCACCAUGUUCCUGACUGCGCUCCUCUGGCGCGGCCGCAUUCCCGGCCGUCAGUGGAUCGGGAAGCACCGGCGGCCGCGGUUCGUGUCGUUGCGCGCCAAGCAGAACAUGAUCCGCCGCCUGGAGAUCGAGGCGGAGAACCAUUACUGGCUGAGCAUGCCCUACAUGACCCGGGAGCAGGAGCGCGGCCACGCCGCGGUGCGCAGGAGGGAGGCCUUCGAGGCCAUAAAGGCGGCCGCCACUUCCAAGUUCCCCCCGCAUAGAUUCAUUGCGGACCAGCUCGACCAUCUCAAUGUCACCAAGAAAUGGUCCUAAUCCUGAGUCGUCACCCUUGGAUUUUAUGGAUCACGGAGCUGACCAUCUUUACCUGGUCCUGGAACUGAAAAACUGUAGCUUGUGUGAAAAUGAGCCUUUGGACCAGUCUUUAUUAAAACAAACAAACAUGAGUAGUCUGCAUAUCGAAUAUCUAGAGCUCUAAACCCCCAAUACUUAAAAGUCUAAUUGCUGUCCUGUGGUUUCAUUAGUCUGAUAGGAAGAUAGGGAUUUCCUCAGUCACAGAUGAUAUUUUGAAGGAAAGCUGCAAUAAAGCCACAAUGAUUUGAGGUCUUUGCUUAAGUAUGAGAUACUUGAUGGGGGCUUUAUCAUGCAACAUUAGUUUGCUUACCUUAAGAAUUGCCCAAAAAUGAAAGAAAAUAUGAGCUUUUCAGUUAAACAUACUCCUAAAAACAUUUUCCGGGAUUUUACUACUAAAAUUGGACAUUUAAGCGAAGUAAAAGAGGCCGGGUGCGGUGGCUCACGCCUGUAAUCCCAACACUUUAGGAGUCCAAGGCGGGCGGAUCACUUGAGGUCAGGAGUUCAAGACCAGCUUGGCCAAGGUGAUAAAACCCGUCUCUACUAAUACAAAAAAAAUUAGCUGGGUAUGUUGGUGCAGGCUUGCAAUCCCAGCUACUUGGGACGCUGAGGUGGGAGGAUCGCCUGAACCUCAGAGGCAGAGGUUGCAAUGAAGCGGAGGUUGCAGUGAGCCGAGAGCAUGCCGCUGCACUCCAGCCUGGGAGACUGCAUCUCAAAAAAGAAAAAUAAACGAAGUAAAAGAUAUUUAUCAGAGCUGUUACAGGAAGGUGUAUUUUUUAGCUAUUUUGGCAGGGUGCUGUGGUGCUUGCAUGUAGUCCCAGCUAUUCAGGAAUAUUGCUUGAGUCCAGCUUGGGCAACAUAGCGAGACCCUAUCUAAAAUAACAAUAAUAUAUGGCCAGGCGGGAUGGCUCACGCCUGUAAUCCCAGCACUUUGGGAGGCUGAGGCGGGCAGAUCACUUGAGGCCAGGAGUUCAAGACCAGCCCAACCAACAUGGUGAAACCCUGUCUCCACUGAAAAUACAUAAAAUUAGCCGGGUGCAGUGGUGAGGCCUGUAAUCCCAGCUACUCAGGAGGCUGAGGCAGGAGAAUCGCUUGCACCCAGGAGGUGGAGGCUGCAGUAAGUCGAGAUUGUGUCACUGCACUCUAGCCUGGGCGACAGAAAAAGAAAAUUUAGGUGGGGAAAAAAAUCAGAAUUGCGUCUGUGGGAACAGGAAUAAAGGAGAAACCACUAUUGACUGGGAAGACACACAAAGAACUUUGUCAAAGUUGUAUGGCUGAGGCCCACACGGUGGCUCACUUCUGUAAUCCCAUCACUUUGGGAGGCUUAGGCAGAAGGAUCACCUGAGAUCAGGAGUUCCAGACCAGCCUGGCCAACAUGGCGAAACCCCAUCUCUACUAAAAAUACAAAAAUUAGCCGGGCGUGGUGGCUUACGCCUGUAAUCCCAGCACUUUGGGAGGCCAAGGUGGGCGGAUCACAAGGUCAGGAGUUCGAGACCAGCCUGGCCAAUAUGGUGAAACCCCAUCUCUACUAAAAAUAUAAAAAUCAGCAAAAAAAAUUUAGCCAGGCUUGGUCAUGCAUGCCUGUAAUCCUAGCUACUGGGAAGGCUGAGGAAGGAGAAUUGCUUGAACCCAGGUGGUGGAGGUUGCAGUGAGCUGAGAUCGUGCCACUGCUCUCCAGCCUGCAUGACGGGAGUGAGACACCAUCUCAAAAAAUACAUAUAAUAAUAUAAAUAAAAAUAUCUUUUUUGAAAAUAAUUUAAUAUACCAUGUAAUUUACCAGUUGAAGAUGUUCGCUUUCAGAAUAUAAUAAAAAUAGUCAAAAA